AAAUCGGCGCUCGACUGGCCUAGGAGCUGUCCGCAGGGAGGUGAGGAGAGGGGCCCGGACGCCCGCGGGGAAGGUGGGGACGGGGGCCCGACGCCCGCGGGGAAGUGGGGACCCAGCCGAGCCGUCCGGGCAGCGGUCGAUCUCUAGAGCCGUCUGCCGGGCAGGCAGCGGACGGGCGCGGCGAGUUGUUGGUCACCAGGCGUCUCCAGGCCGCCGGCCCGCGCCAGCGCCUCAGCCGCAUUUCCAGUCAGAAAGCGAUUUAUGACAAAGUCCAGUUUUCAACAAUGCUGAAAUCAAAUGAUUGCCUGUUUUCUUUGGAAAAUUUGUUUUUUGAAAAACCAGAUGAAGUUGAAAACCAUCCAGACAAUGAAAAGUCAUUGGAUUGGUUUCUCCCUCCUGCUCCAUUGAUUUCAGAAAUUCCAGAUACUCAGGAGUUAGAGGAAGAAUUAGAAAGUCAUAAACUGUUAGGUCAGGAAAAGAGGCCAAAAAUGUUAACAUCAAAUUUAAAGAUAACUAAUGAAGAUACAAAUUAUAUUUCACUAACACAAAAAUUCCAGUUUGCCUUUCCUUCUGAUAAAUAUGAACAGGAUGAUCUAAAUUUAGAAGGGGUAGGUAAUAAUGACUUAUCACAUAUUGCUGGCAAGCUGACAUAUGCUUCUCAGAAAUAUAAAAAUCACAUUGGCACUGAGAUAGCACCUGAGAAGAGUGUUCCUGAUGAUACAAAAUUAGUUAAUUUUGCAGAAGAUAAAGGAGAGAGCACAUCAGUAUUCCGGAAAAGAUUAUUUAAAAUAUCUGACAAUAUACAUGGGAGUGCUUAUUCUAAUGACAAUGAAUUGGACUCUCACAUUGGCUCAGUGAAAAUUGUACAAACAGAAAUGAACAAAGGGAAAUCAAGGAACUAUAGCAAUAGUAAGCAAAAAUUUCAGUAUUCUGCAAAUGUGUUUACAGCAAAUAAUGCUUUUUCUGCUUCUGAAAUCGGAGAAGGCAUGUUCAAAGCACCAUCUUUUUCAGUUGCUUUCCAACCUCAUGAUAUUCAAGAGGUAACAGAAAAUGGUUUAGGUUCCUUGAAGGCUGUCACAGAAAUUCCGGCAAAAUUUAGAAGUAUUUUCAAAGAAUUUCCAUAUUUCAACUAUAUACAGUCCAAGGCCUUUGAUGAUCUUCUUUACACAGAUAGGAAUUUUGUGAUUUGUGCUCCAACUGGUUCUGGAAAAACUGUAGUGUUUGAACUAGCUAUAACAAGAUUGUUAAUGGAAGUACCAUUGCCAUGGUUGAAUAUUAAAAUUGUUUACAUGGCACCAAUAAAAGCCUUGUGCAGUCAGCGUUUUGAUGACUGGAAAGAAAAAUUUGGACCAAUAGGAUUGAAUUGUAAAGAACUUACUGGAGAUACAGUAAUGGAUGAUCUAUUUGAGAUUCAGCAUGCCCAUAUUAUUAUGACAACUCCAGAAAAAUGGGAUAGCAUGACUAGGAAAUGGAGAGACAACUCUUUGGUUCAGCUGGUUCGACUGUUUCUCAUUGAUGAGGUACAUAUUGUAAAAGAUGAAAAUCGUGGUCCAACUCUUGAAGUUGUAGUUAGCAGAAUGAAAACUGUACAGUCUGUUUCUCAGACUUUAAAAAAUACCAGCACUGCUAUUCCAAUGCGAUUUGUAGCUGUAUCUGCAACAAUUCCAAAUGCUGAGGAUAUUGCAGAAUGGCUUUCAGAUGGUGAAAGACCAGCUGUGUGUCUGAAAAUGGAUGAGAGCCAUAGACCAGUGAAACUUCAGAAAGUGGUCCUUGGAUUUCCCUGCAGUAGUAACCAAACUGAGUUUAAGUUUGAUUUAACCCUCAACUACAAAAUUGCCAGUGUUAUACAAAUGUACUCUGAUCAGAAACCCACACUUGUGUUUUGUGCAACAAGGAAGGGUGUGCAACAGGCUGCUUCUGUUCUUGUGAAAGAUGCUAAAUUUAUUAUGACUGUGGAACAGAAACAGAGGUUACAGAAGUAUGCAUAUUCCGUAAGAGAUUCAAAACUGAGAGAUAUCUUAAAAGAUGGUGCUGCUUAUCAUCAUGCUGGUAUGGAGCUGUCAGAUAGAAAAGUAGUUGAGGGAGCUUUUACUGUUGGAGAUUUACCAGUUCUUUUUACUACCAGUACUUUAGCUAUGGGAGUAAAUUUGCCUGCUCACCUAGUAGUUAUAAAAUCUACAAUGCAUUAUGCUGGAGGACUGUUUGAAGAGUACAGUGAAACAGAUAUUCUACAGAUGAUUGGUAGAGCUGGUCGACCUCAAUUUGACACUACAGCUACUGCAGUUAUCAUGACUCGAUUAAGCACAAGGGACAAGUACAUUCAGAUGUUAGCUUGUAGAGACACUGUAGAAAGCAGUUUGCACAGACAUCUUAUUGAACAUUUAAAUGCAGAGAUAGUACUGCAUACCAUCACGGAUGUGAAUAUUGCUGUGGAAUGGAUACGAUCAACUCUGCUUUAUAUCAGAGCCUUGAAAAAUCCAUCUCAUUAUGGUUUUGCAUCUGGAUUGAACAAAGAUGGAAUUGAAGCAAAAUUACAAGAAUUAUGUUUGAAGAAUCUGAAUGAUUUAUCAUCCCUGGACUUAAUAAAGAUGGAUGAAGGUGUUAAUUUCAAACCAACUGAAGCAGGAAGAUUGAUGGCUUGGUAUUAUAUUACAUUUGAGACAGUGAAGAAAUUUUAUACAAUCAGUGGAAAAGAAACCUUAUCAGAUCUGGUUACAUUGAUAGCUGGCUGCAAGGAAUUUCUAGAUAUACAGUUAAGGAUAAAUGAAAAGAAAACACUGAAUACUUUGAACAAAGAUCCAAAUCGGAUAACUAUCAGAUUUCCAAUGGAAGGAAGAAUUAAAACAAGAGAAAUGAAAGUAAAUUGUCUUAUUCAGGCUCAACUAGGAUGCAUUCCCAUACAAGAUUUUGCUUUGACACAAGAUACCGCAAAGAUUUUCAGACAUGGCUCCCGAAUUACAAGAUGGUUGUCAGAUUUUGUAGCUGCUCAAGAAAAGAAGUUUGCUGUACUAUUGAAUAGUUUGAUUUUAGCUAAAUGUUUUAGGUGUAAACUUUGGGAAAACUCUCUGCAUGUAUCCAAACAACUGGAAAAAAUUGGUAUAACAUUGUCAAAUGCAAUCGUAAAUGCUGGUUUGACUUCCUUUAAAAAAAUAGAAGAGACAGAUGCAAGGGAACUUGAAUUGAUUUUAAACAGACAUCCCCCCUUUGGAACCCAGAUAAAAGAAACUGUGAUGUAUCUACCAAAAUAUGAACUUAAAGUGGAACAGAUUACAAGAUAUAGUGAUACGACGGCAGAAAUAUUAGUGACUGUUAUAUUAAGAAAUUUUGAACAGCUACAAACUAAAAGAACAGCAUCGGAUUCUCACUAUGUUACCUUAAUCAUAGGUGACGCAGAUAAUCAAGUAGUUUAUCUGCACAAGAUUACGGAUUCUGUUUUGCUAAAAGCUGGAAGUUGGGCUAAAAAGAUUGCUGUGAAAAGAGCUCUUAAAUCUGAAGAUCUUAGCAUAAAUCUAAUAAGUUCUGAAUUUGUUGGGCUUGAUAUUCAGCAGAAACUUACAGUCUUUUACUUAGAACCCAAGAGGUUUGGAAAUCAAAUCACUAUGCAAAGAAAAUCUGAAACACAGAUUUCCCAUUCUAAACAUUCAGACAUAUCUACAAUAGCAGGACCUAAUAAAGGAACGACUGCCAGCAAAAAACCUGGGAACCGAGAAUGCAAUCAUCUUUGUAAAAGUAAACAUACAUGUGGACAUGACUGCUGUAAAAUUGGAGUUGCACAGAAGUCAGAAAUUAAAGAGUCAACAAUUUCUUCAUAUUUAUCUGAUUUAAGAAACAGGAAUGCUGUUUCAUCUGUUCCUCCAGUUAAACGUCUGAAGAUACAGAUGAAUAAAUCUCAAAGUGUGGACCUUAAAGAGUUUGGUUUUACUCCAAAACCUUCCCUUCCUAGUAUAUCAAGGUCAGAAUAUUUAAACAUAUCUGAAUUGCCUAUAAUGGAGCAGUGGGAUCAGCCUGAAAUCUAUGGAAAAGUUAGACAAGAACCAUCUGAAUAUCAAGACAAAGAAGUUUUGAAUGUGAACUUUGAAUUGGGAAAUGAAGUUUGGGAUGAUUUUGAUGAUGAAAACUUAGAAGUUACUAGCUUUUCAACUGAUACUGAGAAGACAAAAAUAUCAGGAUUUGGAAACACUUUGAGUUCAAGUACCAGGGGAAGUAAGCUACCCCUUCAAGAGUCAAAGAGCAAAUUCCAAAGAGAAAUGUCAAACAGUUUUGUUUCAUCACAUGAGAUGUCGGAUAUUUCUUUAUCAAAUUCUGCUAUGCCCAAGUUCAGUGCAUCCUCCAUGACAAAAUUACCUCAACAAGCCGGAAAUGCAGUUAUUGUCCAUUUUCAAGAAAGAAAACCACAAAAUCUGUCACCAGAGAUUGAGAAGCAAUGCUUUACUUUCUCUGAAAAAAACCCAAAUUCUUCAAAUUAUAAAAAAGUGGAUUUUUUUAUUAGAAACAGUGAAUGUAAAAAGGAAGUUGAUUUCAGUAUGUAUCAUCCUGAUGAUGAAGCUGAUGAAAUGAAGUCUUUAUUGGGAAUAUUUGAUGGUAUUUUCUAAAACAAACAAAUACUUUUUAUAUUGAUAAGAGAAAGAAUAAAGACACCUAAUCACAAAGCAUGCUUUUUAUUUUUAAAAAGUAGUUCAUAAUUGUUCGGAUUUUUUUCUCCUGUAUUUGAUUAGCUUUGUUCACUUUUUGCAACAAAAUGUAUGGGCCGAUUUAUUUUCCCAUUAUAUUGUAACUUCUUGAAAAGCUCUUUUACAGUGGCUUUGUUUCAAUAAGCCCUUAAGUUAAGGGCUGAUUGCACUUAGAAAUAAGUUGCACUUAGAAAUAAUUAUUUGGCUAUUAAUUGGAUUUUGACAAGAACCAAUGUAAAAUUUCAUUUUUAUAUUUUCUUAACAAGAAGAAAAAUAUUCUAUGAAAGCAAAGUAAUGCUAACUUAAUGAAUCUGCUUAUUGUAUGGAUUAAUCACUAAUAUUAUUCCCAUGUAUUUUGUUUUACUAAAGAUUUUUAAGAAUCCAGUGGCUAUUUGAACCUACUGUUAUCUAACUUUGAGCAACAAUAAAUGAAACAUUAAUCAGUA